GAGGAGUGAUCAUGGCUACCUCAGAGCUGAGCUGCGAGGUGUCGGAGGAGAACUGUGAGCGCCGGGAGGCCUUCUGGGCAGAAUGGAAGGAUCUGACACUGUCCACACGGCCCGAGGAGGGCUGCUCCCUGCAUGAGGAGGACACCCAGAGACAUGAGACCUACCACCAGCAGGGGCAGUGCCAGGUGCUGGUGCAGCGCUCGCCCUGGCUGAUGAUGCGGAUGGGCAUCCUCGGCCGUGGGCUGCAGGAGUACCAGCUGCCCUACCAGCGGGUACUGCCGCUGCCCAUCUUCACCCCUGCCAAGAUGGGCGCCACCAAGGAGGAGCGUGAGGACACCCCCAUCCAGCUUCAGGAGCUGCUGGCGCUGGAGACAGCCCUGGGUGGCCAGUGUGUGGACCGCCAGGAGGUGGCUGAGAUCACAAAGCAGCUGCCCCCUGUGGUGCCUGUCAGCAAGCCCGGUGCACUUCGUCGCUCCCUGUCCCGCUCCAUGUCCCAGGAAGCACAGAGAGGCUGAGAGGGACUGUGACUUGGGCUCCGCUGUGCCCGCCCUGGGCUGGGCCCUUCCUGGCUAGGACUGUGGAGGGGAGCUGCUGGCCAUGGCUGCUUUGUAGUUUGCCCAGAGUUGGGGGCUAGGGGAGGGGGGAGCCAGAGGCCAGGAUGCCUGAGCCCCCUGAGUUCCCAAAGGGAGGGUGGCAGAGACAGUGGGCACUAAGGGUGGAGAGUUGGGGGCCAGCACAGCUGAGGACCCUCAGCCCCAGGAGAAGGGACAAAAGGUACUGGUGAGGGCAAGAGGUGCCUGGGAGGAGUGGCCCUGAUCCAGGAAAAUGUGAGGGGAAUCUGGAACGCUCUAGGCAGAAGAAGCUGGGAGGGAGGGGGAGGUGAAAAGGGCAGAGGCAAGGAUGGUGGGGCCCCCAGCACCCUCUGUUAGUGCCGCAAUAAAUGCUCAAUCAUGUGCCAGA